AGUUUUUUUCAGUUGUCACUGCAGAAGCACAUGAUGUCCUAAAGCUCAGCUGUGCUGCUUUGCGUGUGUCUAGAUGGCUGCUGUGCGGCCUGCAUAAACCAAAGAGCAUGUCAUGCUCAACCACAGACAAACAUCUGUUCCACUCCCAUGUCUUCAUUUUACAGAUAGGGAAGACAAGGGCCAGAGAGGGGAAAUGCCUCCAUUAGGGUAAUUCAGAGGGUCUCCUAACCCCCAGAGUACCUGUUCUUCCCGCUCCCACCUCCACCUAAUUCAGGCAUCCCCAAUCCUUCCAAACUAUGUGGCCACUGCAGUAGCAGCACGCAUCAUAGCAGAUGUUCAAGGAAUCUCUGAUACUUGUGUGAUUGCGCAGCCUUCACCACCACACCCUGGAGCUUUGAGGACCUUAGUAUUCACCACAGAUGAACCGGAGACUCCUCAGCCCCCAGGUGCAGCAGGAUUCCAGCUGGUCCAGAAGAAACAAGUGCAGCUGCAUAAGUAAGAGCCCAGCCUGGCCCUCAAUCAGAAUAACAGCCCCUGAGAAAAUGUUUUCCCAAUUUCACUGAUGGAAAAACAAGGAUGGUGAAGCAGUUAGUGACAGAACCAGGGCUGGAACCCGCCACUCCUGACUCCAAACUCCUGGCGCCUUCUACACGGGGCCUCGAGAAAAGCGGGACAGGUAAGUGCAAAGACCCAAACCCAGCGCAGCGCCCAAGCAGGUGCUCAGGCCCGGGCGCUGAACCCUGACGCUGGGCCUGGAGAGCCAGGAGGUGGCAGUCUGCCCGAGGAGGAGGCUUCCCGAGAAGGCAAGGGCAGCGGACCCGGAGAGAAGCCAGUCUCCGAGUGGGGCUGGGGUUCGCCCACCCAAGCUCCGCCUCCCCCAGGCCCAAAAUUCUGUGCACUAGGAGGCUCGAACUUAAGAGCUGACAGCAGGAGAAAAAGGAGGGGGUGAGGGCAAGAAAUACAAAAGUGAUGAAAAGGGAGAAAUGGGGAGGAGAGACCGGACAUAAAGAAGAACGUUGGGAGCCCGGGGAAAGGGGCCGCACUAGAGGUAGGUCGCGAAUCCGAAGAGCUCCGCUCUGCCAGAGCCCCACAAACAAUCCCCCGGUGGCCCCACUCACCCCAGAUGGCGGCGAGUCUGCGGAAAGUUCCUGGGUCAGGGAUGGCUCGGUGCUUCUCAGGGUCCCCAGGACUGCACGGGAUCUGGCAGCUGGAAGCGACCCCCAGGCCUGGAACCUCAGCCCUAGGCAGCUCCUGGAACGUGCCCCGGCUCCUCCGAGCCCCGGGAGGCGGGAGAGCGCAGGAGCGGCCAGGACGCGCUGCUGGCUCUGGAAUGCGCGGCUGCUGGGGACCGCCCCCGGAACGCCCGGUCCCGGGGCCCCGGCAACUCCAGCUCAGCUCCUCCUCCAGCGUCCCCUGCGGGCUGCGUUCGGGGAGAAAGGAACCUGCGAGAGAAGGGAGAGACCAGGGCGUCUCGGGCUCCCCUUCCACGUUGCCACACACUCGCCGCGUAGCCGUGGACAUGUCGCUUGGCUUCUGAGGGUCUCCCCUCUCUGGAUUGUAAACCGAGAGGGUUGGCCUAAAAUGUGUCCUCCACGACCUUUCCAGCUAUAGAGUAGACAUGGGAAAGAAAGCCUAGCAAGUAGGUUUGGACAGAGGAGCCGGGACUCAGAUCCUGCUUUGCGAUGUCCGAAGUGUAGGGUCCUUCGGAGGCUUUGCCACUCUGUUUCAUUCUCUGUAAAGUGGGAAAGGUAACACCUGUCUCCCAGUCCUGUUGUGAGGAUUGGUUUAGAGGACCAGUGUGAAGCUGGUUGGUUCUCUGCCAUAACAUGACUUGGAGCAUCCUGUUUAUUUUGUGAUAACAAUGAAAUAGCCCAAUCCAAGGUGAUCAAGAGCCCAUUAGAAUCCAGCAUCUGAGAGGCUUCCCACGCCACUGUGGGUGGCCCAGCUUCCACGCAGGACAAUGCCAAUUCUGUAAUCUUCUGCCCCCUCUAUGUCAUCCAUGGAGUGAGGGGGGACUCCCGUCCCAUGUUGGCACCCACACUUUUUAAUUCACAGUGGUUUUCUUUAAUCUUACUCUUCUGAAAAAAAGGAGCACAAGCCUUGACUAUCAGUGAGACCUUGAGCAGUCUUGGAGCCCAGUAGUGUUUUGGAGGGUUUGGAAAGAGCCAUACUGCCUUCCCCAGGCCUAAAUUUGAUAUGGUGUGGGCCCCGAACUUAGAACUUACUCCAUGCUGUUUCCUCUGAUUCAGGGAUGAGGUCAGCAGAAAUGACCUCUAAAUCAUCAUUAUCACACGCCAGUUUCUUAAGGGAAGGACAGUGAGGAUGAAGGGGAUUCACAUGAGAAAUGAUUUGAGAAAAACCCUAAGGGCUGUCACCCAACAACAUGUUUUAUUCAAAAGAGAUAGUGUGGGAACCUAAAAACAAGGACAACCCAAUUCUGAAUAGUUUAAUACAAAGCUCUCAUUUAAUAGUAAAAAAAGAUUGAAGGAGGACAAUCUUUUUUUUUUUUUUUUUUUUUUUUGAGACGGAGUCUCGCUCUGUCGCCCAGGCUGGAGUGCAGUGGCAUGAUCUCGGCUCACUGCAACAGGAGGACAAUCUUAAUAUGACAUUUUCCCUGGUUAGUGAAGGGGAUGAGAGUUCCUUUGGGUGGACAACUGGUAACUCCAUGUGCCCUGCUGUGAACAUUGGCUUCCCUCUGGGACAAGGCAGAAGCUCAGGCCUGGAGCCAGCUGAGUCCUAGUCUCCCUUUCCAUUUAGCAAUUUAUUAGUAUCUCUUUAAUAUCGACUUGCCCUGGGACCCUAAAAGCAAGCCAGAAAUAAAGUAUGAAUCCCCACAGGAGCAUACCAUGUUAAGUCUGCUGCCUAGGCUAGACUGAUUUUGCAAAGAGAGCACUGAAGGGAAGAAUAAUGGAUGCUGUGUUGGGAUGCAGGAGUGGGGGAAAUAGUCAAUUUCAGCAACAAGCUUUUGUUACAGCAAAAGCCAGAAAACAGCUCACAACUUCCUUGGUCCUCUAUUACAACCACUCCAAAGAGAAAACCAUCAGGACCUGAAAGAAAUAAGUAAUACUCUCUUAGAGAGCCCCUGAUACUUUGGGGAACUUGUACAGAAGAAGUUGUAGUCUAAUGACAUUGGCUGCCAUCAAAAGACGGCCUUGGCCAGGGGCAGUGGCUCAUGCCUGUAAUCCCAGUACUUUGGGAGGCCGAGGCGGGCAGAUCACCUGAGGUCAGGAGUUCGAAACCAGCCUGGCCAACAUGGUGAAACCCUGUAUCUACUAAAAACACAAAAAUUAGCCAGGCGUGGUGGCGGGCGCCUGUAAUCCCAGCUACUGGAGAGGCUGAGGCAGGAGAAUCACUUGAAUCCCAGAAGCGGAGGCUGCAGUGAGCCGAAUUGCCCCACUGCACUCCAGCCUGGGCAAUAGAGUGGGACUCUGUCUCCAAAAAACAAACAAACAAACAAACAAACAAACCACUGCCUAAAGAGGCCCCCAUUAGGAUGCAAUCCAUAGCAAAUACCCUCUUUAAGAAUCAUAUCUACACGAGACAUUUUCUUUUCAUUUUUCACUUGUACAAAUAUAUUUAUUUACUUUUGGGGAAUAAUAUGACAUAUUGUAUUAGAAAUCAGAAAACCAGUAUUUCGAGUCUGUCACCCAGUAGCCCACCCAAGCUCCAUAAAAUAGUAAAAUGAGACCUAUUCCUCACAUCUGGUACAAUUAUGAUGAGUAAAUAUUUUAUUCAUAUACAGCAGACCCCUGAAUAACAUCCUUCUGUUAUAACGUUGAUGAGGAAAAAAAAUUGUUUCCCUGCUGGGAUCACCGUCUGUGUGGCAUUUGCAUGUCCUCCCCAUGUCUUCCUGGGUUUUCUCCAGGUACCCCGGUCAGUUUCCUCCCACAUCCCGAAGAUAUGCAUGUUAGGCAAACUGCUGUGUCUAUGUAGUCCCAGUGUGAACGAUUGUGGGUGUGGGUGAGUCUGCUCUGCGAUGUGAUGGCGUCCUGUCCAGGGCUGGUUACUGCCUCGAGCCCUGAGCUGCCGGGACAGGCUCUGGCCACUGAACUCUAAACUGGAAUAAGCAGGUAAAUAAUUCUCUUCCUUGUUUUUACUAAUCUUUCUUAAAUGUAUGUAUGGUUCACAAUUAUUUCAGUGUUCAAUAUUGGAAGUGUUUUAGUCUUUAUUUAGAAGUUUGGUGGUACUUUUGUUAUCAGAAAUAUGCUGUAGGAACUUAACUCUUCUUUCUGUCCAUUUGUCUAUGGUAAAAUUGGUUUCCUUAUACAUAGUUUCACUCAAAAUCAAAGUGUCCAAAACCUGUUGAGGAGGCUGAGUGAGGACUUACUGUAUUCCUUCAUUCAAAGCUAUUUAUUGAAUAUCUCCUACAUGUUCUAGGCACUAAGGAAGACAAAUUAUCUUUAUUUAUUGUGCUUACAUCUACUGGGAAAAUAUUCACAAAAAAUAAGUAAGCAAAUAAAUAAGCAAGAUGAUACCGGUUUGCGAAACCAUGAAGAACAUAAAGCAAGAUGAUGAGAGAGUGAUGGAGAGUGUUUUAUCAUGGAGAUUGUAGUUAAACUGAAUUUCCUAAAUAGUUUAUAUCAUCAAUGAUUAUGUUACUCUGUAAUAUAUCAACUUAAUUUCCAAGGUCUUUAAUUAACUGAGAAUUUAGAUUGAUACUAAAUCAAGUAAACUGGUGAAUAAUCUUAGCUGCUUGGAUAAUUUCUAAGAAAGAUAGAAUACAAAAACAUUGGUCACCAAGCAUGGUAUUGAACACCAUUUGCACACCUUUGCCUCUUAUUUUUAUAUGUUUGAGAGUUGAUAAACCUUUGGAUUAUAUUAACGUAUAUGUUUUAUUUUACCACUUAAAGAAAUGCAAAAGGAGUCAGCACAGUGACUCACGCCUGUAA